ACUUCACAUGAAAGCCGCUGCUCUUGGUUCCUGAGAUGAUCUCAUCUGAACAUGGCUCCAGCGACCUCAGCCACAGGAACUAGAGACAGCUUGCUUUCUGUCGUGGCAAUGUUUUGAAACUGGCAAAAUCAGAUUUUAUCAUGUGGGCAACCUGCUGCAACUGGUUCUGCCUGGAUGGACAGCCUGAGGAGGUCCCACCACCCCAGGGAGCCAGGAUGCAGGCCUAUUCCAACCCUGGGUACAGCUCCUUCCCUUCCCCAACAGGCUUGGAACCAAGCUGCAAGUCCUGUGGGGCUCACUUUGCAAACACGGCCAGGAAGCAGACCUGCUUGGACUGUAAGAAAAAUUUUUGCAUGACCUGUUCGAGCCAAGUAGGGAAUGGGCCCCGCCUCUGCCUUCUCUGCCAACGGUUUCGAGCUACAGCCUUUCAGCGAGAGGAGCUCAUGAAGAUGAAGGUGAAGGACUUGAGGGACUAUCUCAGCCUCCAUGACAUCUCUACCGAAAUGUGCCGGGAGAAAGAAGAGCUGGUGCUCUUGGUCCUUGGCCAGCAGCCUGUAAUCUCCCAGGAGGACAGGACUCGUGCCUCCACCUUGUCCCCAGACUUUCCUGAGCAGCAGGCCUUCCUGACCCAGCCUCACUCCAGCAUGGUUCCACCUACCUCACCCAACCUCCCCUCUUCAUCUGCACAAGCCACCUCUGUUCCCCCAGCCCAGGUUCAGGAGAAUCAGCAGGCCAAUGGCCAUGUGUCUCAGGAUCAAGAGGAACCCGUCUACCUGGAGAGCGUGGCCAGAGUACCUGCUGAGGAUGAGACCCAGUCUAUUGACUCAGAGGACAGCUUUGUCCCAGGCCGAAGGGCCUCUCUGUCUGACCUGACUGACCUGGAGGACAUUGAAGGCCUGACAGUGCGGCAGCUGAAAGAGAUCUUGGCUCGCAACUUUGUCAACUACAAGGGCUGCUGUGAGAAGUGGGAGCUGAUGGAGAGAGUGACCCGGCUAUACAAGGAUCAGAAAGGACUCCAGCACCUGGUCAGUGGUGCCGAAGACCAAAACGGGGGAGCAGUACCAUCAGGCUUGGAGGAGAACCUGUGUAAGAUCUGCAUGGACUCACCCAUUGACUGUGUUCUUCUGGAGUGUGGCCACAUGGUAACCUGUACCAAGUGUGGCAAGCGCAUGAAUGAAUGUCCCAUCUGCCGGCAGUAUGUAAUCCGAGCUGUGCAUGUCUUCCGGUCCUGAGAGCUUGCAUCGGUUUCUUCAGUGCCUUACAGGGAAAUAGCCUGGGGUGUCUGGGCUCAGGGUUGGCCAGCUUGCAGAGGAGCAAGCUAGUAGAAAUAUUGCAGGGUUCCCAAAACCAGGUCAAGCAAGAUGCCAUGUCACCCCUGAGCAUGCCUGUCUUCCCAGGGGUGUACCUCUUGGCUGGCAAAGCCCAAGGCCAGUGGGAACUUGUAUAAAUCACAUGGGUAUGUUCUUGGUUCAGUGAUCUUGGAGUGAUGAUGGUAACUGAUGAACAGAGAACUUUCCAGAACUUGGGUCCUGUCUUCCUCCCUGAACCUAGACAGUUUCACCCCUCCUCCUGUACCCAACCCAUCCCCACCCCAUAUGGGAGAUGCUUGCCCAUGUGUUUCAUCAAUCAGAAGUCCUCCUCCCCAGCACAUUCGGAUUUAAAUUUCUGGUCUCUCCGGCUUUCUGUGCUUUAACUAUCUUUGCUAAAGUCUCUUGCUACAUUGCCUAAAUCCAUUUGUUUCUUUGGACCAAAAAUGUUAGUUUACCAGACCGAUAGUGGUCCUUAGGACAGAUUUUAGACCAGUAAACUUAUCUUUGGUGAGAAAUGAAAUACAAAUGCUAUAGAAAAAUUUCAAAGUUGUUAAAAGCCACUUCAUUAAAUGCUGGGAUUGGAAGCUGUUGGUCUCCUGACCUGACUCUGGGAGCCAACAAAACAUCAGGCUCCCAAACUGCUGGGAAAUUUGUUUCUGUCUGCAAGGGAUAGUGCGUGCAUAAUCCCUGCUGCUGCUUCUCUUGGGACCUGAUUUGCACCAUCCUUAGUUUAUGCGGAAAGGGGAAGCAAUGGGUGGAGGCAGUGGCCUUCUCCUUAAUUUUGGCUUGGCUUCUGAUCCUUUUCCCAACUAGAAGUCUUAAGCCACUUUUCGCUGAAAAUGAAAUCCCUCCCUUAUCCAUGGUAGUUUUAAAUUUGGUUUCAUUGAAGAAAUAGAUUUAGGCAAAGAGCCUGUGCUCUUCUCUGGCCAGACUGCUGUUGAAGUUCCUGGAGAGCAAAUGUUAAGACAGAGCACUUAAGAGCUUUCAGGAGGUACUGAAUGAGACUGGAUUCUGUUGUAAGCCGACAGUUCAAGUCUUUAUUUCCCAGGUUGGUGGGGAGUGAGGAGACCCUACUUUCAUUCCCUUUCCUAGCCCACUGAUUUUUGGGGGCAGGUCAGGGAGAAAGCAUUUUUUUUUUUUUUUUGAGUCUCACUCUGUUGCCCAGGCUGGAGUGCAGUGGUACAGUCUUGGCUUACUGCAACCUCCACCUCCCAGGUUCAAGCUAUUCUCCUGCCUUAGCCUCCAGAGUAGCUGGGAUUAUAGGCGCCCACCACCACACCAGGCUAAUUUUUGUAUUUUUAGUAGAGACGGGGUUUUACCAUGUUCACCAGGCUGGUCUUGAACUCUUGACCUUAUGAUCCGCCCGCCUCAGCUUCCCAAAGUGCUGGGAUUACAGGCGUGAGCCACCACACCCAGCAGGAGAAACCAUUUUCUAGGCUCUUUAGGAAGGACCAUGCAAUGAGUAGGUGAUGUAUUUGAGCCCUCACAGUCUUUACACCCCUAGAGGAGCUGGAGGACUUAAGAGUUUGCUGCAGAAGCGUGGCCAAGCACAAAACACAUGAUCAGGAAAGCAGAGUGUUUUCCCAUUACCAAUGGAUGAACUAUGCAAACCCUAAACGCCUUGGCAGACACCUCCCACCCCUUACCCCUCCCAUGCAGCUGAAAAAUCUGAGACUAGAACCAAUCAUGACUCUGGAUGGCAGAGGGAAACCUCUAAAGGGACUUAUUACAUUGGUACAGACAUAUUUAUGCUUUCUUCCAUCACCAACCACUAAACCCCUUUGGAGGAAUGAAAUAACUGCAUAAACUAGUCAACUGAACACUGGGCCACUUACCUCAAUGUUAUACAAAGUCCUGGAUGAUUUGAUUCUGAACCACAGCCUUUGCAGGAGUUGGGGGAAUCAGAUUUGCUCAUGAAGACAUCCCUUUCCACUUUUGUCAUGGGCAGUAAAUACUAUAGUUUACAAUGCCUACCAAUUAGCAAAGGAUCAUUCAUUCAGCUACUCAGUUCCUCUGUAAAACAGGUCUAUGUAUGUGCAAUUCAGCUAAGAUCUAGCAGUAACUUAAGGGCAGAAGCUGGCUCUCUACUUACAACCUGCUUUCUCUGCUGAAGCCUUACCUCCUCUUCAGUUUCCCUCCUAGACACAAAUCGAAAAUAAUAUACUGAUAGCUGGUUAGUAACCUCAGUAAGAAUUAAAACUGAGGUUGUUUACUCAUUUUGCCUUUAAAUCUUUUAUCCCCUUUUGGUGAAGGUUUCCCUUUAGGAAAAAAGGUGUCAAACAACCCUGAUUUUUUUUUUUUUUGCAUCAUUUUUAUUACACCAAAUUAAAGUUGGGAGUUCCAAGAUCCCAUUCCAGUUAAUAUUUAACCAAGGUCUAAAAUUUGAUUUUUUUUAAAUCUUUGAAUCCUCCCUUCUGCCCCUCAUGGAUCCUUGGUUUUAAUGAUAUGGAAACAUCUAAUUCUUAGAAUUAUUCCGUAGCUUUUGCUGAUUACUCUGAGAUUUCAGUUAAGACUUGUUUCAAAAGACAGAUAGCUGACUGGUUCAUAAUACAUUGGAAUAGUUGGAUCCAAACUAAUAAGAAUAAGCUGUACAGGAACUAGUGCUCAAUAUACAUUGUAUAAAUUUGUGGAAAUCUCUUGGAUGUGAAUUGUUACUUCAAGUGGCUUUUAUUAAGAUUUUCUCAGACUUACUUGGAGGUUAAAGCAAACCCAAAUGUGUAUUAUUUUGUUACAGAGCUCUGCUUUAUAAUUUUGUAAUAAAGUUUCAAUACAGACACCUGUCCUGUCUGGUGCGAGGAUGUUAGAGGUUGAUAGGACUGACAAAAGAGCCUGACAGUGGUUCAUGCUAUAAUUUCCACACUUUAGGAGGCCAAGGUGGGAAGACUGCUUGAGCUCAGGAGUUUGAGACCAACCUGGGCAAUGUAGUGAGACCUUGUCUCUACUUAAAAAAACAAACAAGGGCCGGGUGCGGUGGCUCACGCCUGUAAUCCCAGCACUUUGGGAGGCUGAGGCGGGCAGAUCACGAGGUCAGGAGAUCGAGACCACCCUGGCUAACACGGUGAAACCCCGUCUCUACUAAAAAUACAAAAAAUUAGCCAGGCGUGGUGGCGGGUGCCUGUAGUCCCAGCUACUCGGGAGGCUGAGGCAGGAGAAUGGUGUGAACCCGGGAGGCGGAGCUUGCAGUGAGCCAAGAUUGCGCCACUGCAGUCCGGCCUGGGCGAAAGAGCGAGACUCUGUCUCAAAAAACAAAACAAAAAAAAACACAAACAAAAAACCCAAAAAAACCAAAAAAUUAGCCGUGCAUGGUGGUGCAUGUGGGUAGUCCCAACUACUUGGAAGGCUGAGGUGGGAGGAUCACUUGAGCCAGGAGAUUGAAGCUGCAGUGAGCUCUGAUCGCCACCGCACUCCAGCCAGGGUGACAGAGUGAGACCCUGUAUUAAAAAAAAAAAAAAAUUGACAACUGAUAAACCACAAGCUAAUCCUGGGAUGUGCACAUGGCCUGGGAUUAGCCUGUGGUUGGGCCAAGUGACCUUGGUCAAGAUGCUCAGUGUUGUUGUAACUAACUAACUUGCUCAAGACCACAAAUGUAAUAUAUGGAAGAGGCCAUGGAACAACCUAGAAGAGAAUGAGAGCUGGGUAGGUAAAGGAUGAAUCCCAAGACCAAUUGGGUUGAAGCACCAAGUGAGUUCAGAUAUUUACACUGAUCUAGAAGAGAUGGGCCUUAAAGAACUGAAAUCUGAGGACAGUUAGUAUGCCCAGUUAGGUCUUCAGGUUACCCUGGGAGAUACAUGGUACCUUUUGGAUACAGCUGUAGUACAGCUGGACUAUGGCUCAGAAAAGGUUGGCCCAGGCUGGGCGCCAUGGCUCACGCCUGUAAUCCCAGCACUUUGGGAGGCUGAGGUGCGUGGAUGACUCGAGGCCAGGAGUUUGAGACCAGUCUGGACAACAUGGCGAAACGUGGUCUCUACUAAAAAUACAAAAACUUAGCUGCGAGUGAUGGUGUGUGCCUGUUUGUUAAGUCUUAGCCACUUGGGAGGCUGAGGCAUGAGAAUUGCUUGUGAACCCGGGAAGCAGAGGUUGCAGUGAGCUGAGAUUGCACCACUGCACUCCAGCCUGAAUGACAGAGCAAGAGUCUGUUUAAAAAAAAAAAAAAGGUUGGCCCAGCCUCGUGACAGACUGCUGUGUGUGCGCAGGCUUGUACAAACCUCCCUGACCAGGCGCCCAAGGAGCAGGGAAAAGACUACUGAGAAUGCAGCCCCUGGGAGAACAAGAUUAUGUGUCCAUCUGCUGUGACUGAGAAGAGAAAGGAAUCUUGCCAAAAGGGCAUAAAGGAUCGAGGAUGAGCCACAACACUUUGCUCACAUUGCCCUAGGGAGCUGACCUGUUCAGCACCCAGUGAUGACCUCUGCUUGAUGCCAGCCAGCAGCAUGUAGAGGUUCAGAAGAGGGAGGCCUCCAGCAUUCUGCUGGAGAGAUUUAUGAUGAUGAUGUUGAGGGCUGCAUUGAAAUACAUGAAAGAAAUACAUGAAAGGAUACAAAAUAGUAUAUACAGUCAGAUCUCAGCAGCAAAGACUGGAAGAAAAUACAUAAAAAACCACUGACAUUGAAAUGGCAAUAACACACACUAAGGCAGAGAAGGGACAAGAUGAUCACCUGCAGCCAGCAGAGGCCCUUUCCUGUGAGUGUGCACUCUGGGUGUAAGCAACCAAUAAGGGCAAGUGGGGCUGGGUCCAGGUUGGAGAGGACAGUGCCUUUGGCAGGAUCCUGAGGAGACAGCCUUGUUCUGCUGCCCUGUCCGGUUGUUUGUUUGGCCUGAGGCUGAAGAGAGAAAUGGAAAUCUAUGUAGGUCAGUACUCAAAGGAGGAGCAGCUUUUUGUCUCCAUAGAGGAUGGAAUAAAAAGUAUCUUAUUCCUAAUACUGAAGCAAGGCUGAAUGGUGCCUAUUCAAAAACACCAAAUGUCCUGGGCUAGAGUCAGGAAAGUAAACCCCUCCCCCGUGCUGUCCCUACUCCCCCAACAUACACAUUUUAAACAGUAGGUGGAAGCCAAAGUCAAUCAGAUCAAAGUUGGGGGGGGGCGGUGGGGUGGCCAGGGGGCGCAGUGGUCCUUGAUCUUAUAGGUCCAGAGCCUGUUAAUUUGUUCAUAAGGUGAGAACUGACCCUCAAGAGCUGGAAGGAUUGGGACAUGGCAGCCAGUUUACAACCAUAUGGUGUCCUGAUGAGCCUGCACUCAGAGUGGAGUGUUGGCUGGAACAUGCACACCUGCAACUGAGGGUUCUAAAGUCAUAGGUUAGGCCCUUCUCCCGGGUAGGGUCUGGACAUGCACACCAGGAGUGACGUUCCCAACUCUAGAUAACUAUGUGCUAGGCUCUGGGCUAAGUGCUUUACAUAAUGUUGCUCAGGACAACAGGACAACCCUAUGAUUUAGGUGCACCCAUUCUACUUGGAGGGAUUGAGGCUUAGAUGUUAACGUAACUUGCCUAAGGUUAGAGCCAUUAAGUUUCAGGAGUCUGAUCUGAACUCCGUCUACACCUGCACUGUCCAGUGUGGUAGUCACUAGUGACAUGUGACCAUUUGAAGUUGAAUUAAAAUAAGAACUUCAGUUCCUUAGUUGUGCCAGCUUCAUUUCAAUUGCUCAGCAGCUGUCUGUGGCUAGUUUGGUUGGAUACUGCAGAUUUAUGGAUAUUUCCACUGCUGCAAAAAGUUCUAUUGAAUAGCACUUGUCUACACUAAAUUGUCUCUCUUCCUUUUGUUCUUCAAAUAAAUCAGCCUCAGGUAGCACAGGAGCUGUUCUUUGUAAGCAGGUUGUAUGGAUCUGUUCUCAGGUGUGGAUUUUUAUUUUUUUCCCUGCAGAUAUGGAGUAUAUUUUCUUUAAGAAAUUAAAAACUAAGAAGAAAAUGCCA